UUUGGGAAAGGAGAGGAUUGGAAUACGGAAAUGGAUUAAGGAUGAGGCCCGCCGGGGGCUUGAGAGGGAGGAAGAGCAGACCUUCUCUGGGUCUGGAGCCGCCUGAGGACACAGACCAGAGGAAAUGAAUACAGACUGCACCUCCCCAGCCGCUCUCCACCCCUCCCCUGGCUCUUCUACCCUCUCCAGCCCCAGACCCAUUUCUUCCCUUUCUUGCUCUGGCCAUUGCUCCCCCUUCCCCUCCUAGAUCCCAAGCCCGCACAACAUCUCAAACAAGAGUCCUCGAUUCAAAAGCCAGAUGCCGACCCCCCUUCCUCCUGGAUCUGGCUCAGGGCAGCAGCUCCACCCCGGGACAGAGAGAGCAUUGAUUGUAGCUGCAGCCGCCGCGGGAUCCUAGCCUCACCCGUCAAGGGGCUGAGCGCCAGGGACCCUGAACUCGUCUAGUGGUGCGCCCUGCGCACCCGGGCGCACUCAACCGAGGCAAUGCCCUGCGCGCUCUCGCGGGUGCACGCCCCUUCUGUGGCCUCUCCUGGGCGAGCACUGCUCUGCAGAUAGGCUAGACUACCGGCUCCGCGUCGCCUCGCCAAGGGUUGGUUCAGCCAAGGCUGCAAAAAACAAAAAAAGACCAGGCAGACAGCCUAUCCAGGGUGGCUAUUGAAACUGGGCUGGAAAACUGCAGUCCCAGGAACUCCAGAGAGCUGGACAUUGGGAAGCAUCCUUGGCUCACAUACAAUCGGAGAUCACUAUGUCUUUCUCUCCUCCAGGAACACGAUUAGCUUGUGUCCUAUCCAGAUAGGAAUAGAUGCUCCCUAUCUGGGAGCAUCCUUAGCUAUGGUGAAUGGUAUCUAGCCAUCCACUGGGGAUGGCGAGUGACUUAGGGAUUUGUGUCUCACGUAUAUGAAGCAGUCAUCGCCAGAUGUUGGUUGUUUUUCUUAACCCCCAUCAUAACCCGAUCCAGGACUGAGAUCCCAGAACCAUGAACCUGGCCAUCAGCAUCGCUCUCCUGCUAACAGUCUUGCAGGUCUCCCGAGGGCAGAAGGUGACCAGCCUAACGGCCUGCCUAGUGGACCAGAGCCUUCGUCUGGACUGCCGCCAUGAGAAUACCAGCAGUUCACCCAUCCAGUACGAGUUCAGCCUGACCCGUGAGACAAAGAAGCACGUGCUCUUUGGCACUGUGGGGGUGCCUGAGCACACAUACCGCUCCCGAACCAACUUCACCAGCAAAUACAACAUGAAGGUCCUCUACUUAUCCGCCUUCACUAGCAAGGACGAGGGCACCUACACGUGUGCACUCCACCACUCUGGCCAUUCCCCACCCAUCUCCUCCCAGAACGUCACAGUGCUCAGAGACAAACUGGUCAAGUGUGAGGGCAUCAGCCUGCUGGCUCAGAACACCUCGUGGCUGCUGCUGCUCCUGCUCUCCCUCUCCCUCCUCCAGGCCACGGAUUUCAUGUCCCUGUGACUGGUGGGGCCCAUGGAGGAGACAGGAAGCCUCAAGUUCCAGUGCAGAGAUCCUACUUCUCUGAGUCAGCUGACCCCCUCCCCCCAAUCCCUCAAACCUUGAGGAGAAGUGGGGACCCCACCCCUCAUCAGGAGUUCCAGUGCUGCAUGCGAUUAUCUACCCACGUCCACGCGGCCACCUCACCCUCUCCGCACACCUCUGGCUGUCUUUUUGUACUUUUUGUUCCAGAGCUGCUUCUGUCUGGUUUAUUUAGGUUUUAUCCUUCCUUUUCUUUGAGAGUUCGUGAAGAGGGAAGCCAGGAUUGGGGACCUGAUGGAGAGUGAGAGCAUGUGAGGGGUAGUGGGAUGGUGGGGUACCAGCCACUGGAGGGGUCAUCCUUGCCCAUCGGGACCAGAAACCUGGGAGAGACUUGGAUGAGGAGUGGUUGGGCUGUGCCUGGGCCUAGCACGGACAUGGUCUGUCCUGACAGCACUCCUCGGCAGGCAUGGCUGGUGCCUGAAGACCCCAGAUGUGAGGGCACCACCAAGAAUUUGUGGCCUACCUUGUGAGGGAGAGAACUGAGCAUCUCCAGCAUUCUCAGCCACAACCAAAAAAAAAUAAAAAGGGCAGCCCUCCUUACCACUGUGGAAGUCCCUCAGAGGCCUUGGGGCAUGACCCAGUGAAGAUGCAGGUUUGACCAGGAAAGCAGCGCUAGUGGAGGGUUGGAGAAGGAGGUAAAGGAUGAGGGUUCAUCAUCCCUCCCUGCCUAAGGAAGCUAAAAGCAUGGCCCUGCUGCCCCUCCCUGCCUCCACCCACAGUGGAGAGGGCUACAAAGGAGGACAAGACCCUCUCAGGCUGUCCCAAGCUCCCAAGAGCUUCCAGAGCUCUGACCCACAGCCUCCAAGUCAGGUGGGGUGGAGUCCCAGAGCUGCACAGGGUUUGGCCCAAGUUUCUAAGGGAGGCACUUCCUCCCCUCGCCCAUCAGUGCCAGCCCCUGCUGGCUGGUGCCUGAGCCCCUCAGACAGCCCCCUGCCCCGCAGGCCUGCCUUCUCAGGGACUUCUGCGGGGCCUGAGGCAAGCCAUGGAGUGAGACCCAGGAGCCGGACACUUCUCAGGAAAUGGCUUUUCCCAACCCCCAGCCCCCACCCGGUGGUUCUUCCUGUUCUGUGACUGUGUAUAGUGCCACCACAGCUUAUGGCAUCUCAUUGAGGACAAAGAAAACUGCACAAUAAAACCAAGCCUCUGGAAUCUGUCCUCGUGUCCACCUGGCCUUCGCUCCUCCAGCAGUGCCUGCCUGCCCCCGCUUCGCUGGGGUCUCCACGGGUGAGGCUGGGGAACGCCACCUCUUCCUCUUCCCUGACUUCUCCCCAACCACUUAGUAGCAACGCUACCCCAGGGGCUAAUGACUGCACACUGGGCUUCUUUUCAGAAUGACCCUAACGAGACACAUUUGCCCAAAUAAACGAACAUCCCAUGUCUGCUGACUCACCUGGCUGGAACAACAUGCUUACUGCCAACAUGUGGGCCGAACCACAUGGCCCUGGCUCUGGAAUGCACAAGUGGCUUUGCGUGAAUCUGCGCUAAGCUAUGCAGUCUGCUUUUUCUUCUCAGCUCUGGUAGUUCUUCAGAAAUGUACCCUCCAGGCACAUCCACUAUUGCGAGGGUGAGCACGAAGGGUGGGAGAUGCCCAUGUCCUCAAGGCAUCACUUCCUAAAUCCAAAAGCAUCGGCAGGAGAAAGGACUGGGGACAAAUACUGUCCCUUCGGGAGUAGGGAGGGAACACUGAGGCCCAUCCCUGGCUCCUUCCCUAAAAGUAGAGUAAAAUGGAAGCGAGCAUCCUGGGAUUGGGGGCAAGAGGGGGACCGCAGGGUAGCUGUGGGUUCCAACUGCUGUCAGAGUCAGAGAGGCAGCCCCAAGCCAGCCUCCCUGCUUUGCCAGGGAAUUUGGGGGAGGAAGGUGACAGCUGCCCAGAGGCUGACUCAUCUGAUAUUUAGCACUGGGUAGGAUGAUUGUUUCUGAGCAUUUUUCUUAAAGGCCUCAGAUCUAAAUUAUGCCACCGGCUCCCACUCUUGCUACCUCCCGUCAACUUCUCUGCCUUGCCUUCCACCCCUGUAGUUACCAUACACAGAGGAGGAGGAGCUGUCCUUGUCCCAGGUUGGGAGGCUGACAACCCCUUAGCAAGAUGCUGCCAGCCCAGAGCUCUCCAAGGGGAGGAACACCCCUGAGACUCAGGCCCCUCUCCUUCAGCCCUGCUUGGGCUGCAAGCGCCGUGCCAAGGAAAGGCAUCUUGGUGAGAAGAGCUGCUGUGGGGGAAGGGAGAUCAAAUGCCAGAGAAAUGUGGGGUGCCCCACCCUCAGGAUAGUAAAAGAGUAUGGAGGUAUUUCUGGAAGGAAAUGAGCGGCACUGUGUGAAGCCUCGCACCUGUGUGACACUUCCUAUGGGGUCUUUGUCACACUCUAGUACUAUGUCCCUGAAGAGUUUAGCAGCCACACUCUUAGAAGGGUGCUGGGAGAUGGUGUUGCCCUCUGCAGCCAUGUUUAGGGGAGCGGAACCUGAGGCCCACAGUGGGUGAGAUUAGCUCAAGAAGCCACAGAGGCCACCAGAGGGCCACGGACUUCGGAAAGGAGAAGAGAAGAACAGGGCAUCAGGCCUCACAACGCAAACCUACCCAGAGAUGGGCACAGUGGCUCAUGCCUGUAAUCCCACCACUUUGGGAAGAGGCGGAUCGCUUGAGGUCAGGAGUUCGAGACUAGCCUCGAAACCCUAUCUCUACUAAAAAUACAAAAAUUAGCCAGGCAUGGUGGCCUGCGCCUGUAAUCCCAGCUACUCAGGAGGCUGAGGCAGGAGAAUCACUUGAACCCGGGAGGCGGAGGUUGCAGUGAGCCAAGAUUGCACCACUGCACUCCAGCCUGGGAGAUAGAGUGAGACUCCAUCUCAAAAAAAUAAAAAAUAAAAUAAACCUACCCGGAAUGACCAUGCUGAGGACUGGGAGCCCGCAGACUUUCAGCCACAGGCCGCGACAGCCGUGGGUCCCUCCCUGGUCAAGUCAGCAGGCCUUGUGGAGGCUGUGGGGUAUCUGUGGUGACUCAGGUAAUUAUAGAGGGCUGGCCCCCAGCCCUGGUUCCUGUACACAUGCCCCAACCCCAUCCCCAUCCACUCCCUCGCCAGUCCUAACCUCUUUCCUGGGUCCCCCCCCUUCAGCACCUAAGUCCAUACCUAGGGCCGUGGAAUUCCCGCUCAAGAGCAACAGAAGCCCCUCUCUGCACCCCCAUUUCUGGACUGGAUUGUCCACUGAGACGCGCAAUGUCUGCAUCUCUGACAUCUAGAGGCUUCCUCGGGAAGGGCAUGGGGAUCUCCGUGAGAUGUGGGGACUUUCACUGGCCAACCAAGAAAUCUACACAGCGUCCGGGGACCUGUGACACACAUCCCUCCCGCCUCCUCAACCUGAUGUCCCUCUCUGAAUCUGCAGCUUUCGUGCUGUGAAGGUGUCUUUACAUGUGAAACAAACAAACCCAAGUCAAGAGUAAAUCAUCUCAUUUACUAGUGAGAAAAUGUUGGAGCUGGAGUCCUUCAGAGAGUCCUGGCCAGGCAAGAGGGCCAUCAGCUCUCUUCUGCUCAACAGGGGCUCUCAGCCUCAGGACACUCUCAGGCCUGGAAUGUCCCCAACACACUCAAGGAGAAACAUGUCCUGUGCAGACCCACAGGAGGCAUCUUUGCCCGGCACAAGGAAGAGCUGGGGUCAGUGGGACCUGUAGAUGUAGACACAUCAUAUGGAGGGUGGGUAGGACCAAUGUGGCAGCUUCAUGGAGGCCAAGUGUGGCUCUGCACCAGGAAGGGGCUGUGAUGGCUGGAGGUGCCCAGCAGUGCAGGCGGGGAGUGCCUGGCAGUGGCGUGGCCAGGUGGAGGCCACCUGUCAAGUUUGCAAUAAAGCAGUUUCCUGAAUUUGGUGAGAA